AGACAAGGUUUUCCAAGCAAGAUGAAGCCCAACAUCAUCUUUGUACUUUCCCUGCUCCUCAUCUUGGAGAAGCAAGCAGCUGUGAUGGGACAAAAAGGUGGAUCAAAAGGCCGAUUACCAAGUGAAUUUUCCCAAUUUCCACACGGACAAAAGGGCCAGCACUAUUCUGGACAAAAAGGCAAGCAACAAACUGAAUCCAAAGGCAGUUUUUCUAUUCAAUACACAUAUCAUGUAGAUGCCAAUGAUCAUGACCAGUCCCGAAAAAGUCAGCAAUAUGAUUUGAAUGCCCUACAUAAGACGACAAAAUCACAACGACAUCUAGGUGGAAGUCAACAACUGCUCCAUAAUAAACAAGAAGGCAGAGACCAUGAUAAAUCAAAAGGUCAUUUUCACAGGGUAGUUAUACACCAUAAAGGAGGCAAAGCUCAUCGUGGGACACAAAAUCCUUCUCAAGAUCAGGGGAAUAGCCCAUCUGGAAAGGGAAUAUCCAGUCAAUAUUCAAACACAGAAGAAAGGCUGUGGGUUCAUGGACUAAGUAAAGAACAAACUUCCGUCUCUGGUGCACAAAAAGGUAGAAAACAAGGCGGAUCCCAAAGCAGUUAUGUUCUCCAAACUGAAGAGCUAGUAGCUAACAAACAACAACGUGAGACUAAAAAUUCUCAUCAAAAUAAAGGGCAUUACCAAAAUGUGGUUGAAGUGAGAGAGGAACAUUCAAGUAAAGUACAAACCUCACUCUGUCCUGCGCACCAAGACAAACUCCAACAUGGAUCCAAAGACAUUUUUUCUACCCAAGAUGAGCUCCUAGUAUAUAACAAGAAUCAACACCAGACAAAAAAUCUCAAUCAAGAUCAACAGCAUGGCCGAAAGGCAAAUAAAAUAUCAUACCAAUCUUCAAGUACAGAAGAAAGACGACUCCACUAUGGAGAAAAUGGUGUGCAGAAAGAUGUAUCCCAAAGCAGUAUUUAUAGCCAAACUGAAGAGAAAGCACAGGGCAAGUCUCAAAAACAGAUAACAAUUCCCAGUCAAGAGCAAGAGCAUAGCCAAAAGGCAAAUAAAAUAUCAUACCAAUCUUCAAGUACGGAAGAAAGACGACUCCACUAUGGAGAAAAUGGUGUGCAGAAAGAUGUAUCCCAACGCAGUAUUUAUAGCCAAACUGAAAAGCUAGUAGCAGGCAAGUCUCAAAUCCAGGCACCAAAUCCUAAGCAAGAGCCAUGGCAUGGUGAAAAUGCAAAAGGAGAGUCUGGCCAAUCUACAAAUAGAGAACAAGACCUACUCAGUCAUGAACAAAAAGGCAGACACCAACAUGGAUCUCAUGGGGGAUUGGAUAUUGUAAUUAUAGAGCAGGAAGAUGACAGUGAUCGUCAUUUGGCACAACAUCUUAACAACGACCGAAACCCAUUAUUUACAUAAACCUACCAUUCGGUAACCAUGUGAAAGGAUGGACCAAUAUCAAGGUGUCAGUUGACCUCAGUGAAUUCUGUGAUGUUUCUGAGAUGCAGACUCCCGUGUAGUUUCAGAUUCUUGGUCCAUGGAUGACACCACCUGCCCAUGCUUCCUUGAAUUAGGCUUUCCUAACCUGAAGCGCCUUCAAACUUCCAAUAAAGAGAUCAUUUUCUGCUUCA